GGACCGGAAGUGCCCGAGGGCGGCCGCAGAACGGUCAAUUUGAGCCGCGUCGAGGUCGGGCUUGGGAAGGGUCAGCGGGAGGCCUGAGGGCGCCGGGCGCUGCGGCAGGCGGGCCCGGGGUCCAGCCGAGAGGGUCCGGGCGCCAGGCAACGCGAUUCGCGCGGGGGUGAACCCGGGGAGGGGGCCGGCCUCCCCGUUCUGGGACCUUUCGCUCCCCUGGGACCUGUGGCCGCCGCCCACAGACCAUGCUCCUGGGGCGCCUGACUUCCCAGCUGUUGAGGGCCGUUCCUUGGGCAGGCGGCCGCCCGCCUUGGCCCGUCUCUGGAGUGCUGGGCAGCCGGGUCUGCGGGCCCCUUUACAGCACAUCGCCGGCCGGCCCAGGUAGGGCGGCCUCUCUCCCUCGCAAGGGGGCCCAGCUGGAGCUGGAGGAGAUGCUGGUCCCCAGGAAGAUGUCCGUCAGCCCCCUGGAGAGCUGGCUCACGGCCCGCUGCUUCCUGCCCAGACUGGAUACCGGGACCGCAGGGACUGUGGCUCCACCGCAAUCCUACCAGUGUCCGCCCAGCCAGAUAGGGGAAGGGGCCGAGCAGGGGGAUGAAGGCGUCGCGGAUGCGCCUCAAAUUCAGUGCAAAAACGUGCUGAAGAUCCGCCGGCGGAAGAUGAACCACCACAAGUACCGGAAGCUGGUGAAGAAGACGCGGUUCCUGCGGAGGAAGGUCCAGGAGGGACGCCUGAGACGCAAGCAGAUCAAGUUCGAGAAAGACCUGAGGCGCAUCUGGCUGAAGGCGGGGCUAAAGGAAGCCCCCGAAGGCUGGCAGACCCCCAAGAUCUACCUGCGGGGCAAAUGAGUCUGGCGCCGCCCUUCCCGCCCGUUGCUGCUGUGAUCCGUAGUAAUAAAUUCUCAGAGGACUCA